ACUUGCUCUGCGCUGAGGUGCUGGGACAGCCAUGGUUUCAGACGAAGAUGAAUUGAAUCUUCUGGUUAUUGUAGUUGAUGCCAACCCAAUUUGGUGGGGAAAGCAAGCAUUAAAGGAAUCUCAGUUCACUUUAUCCAAAUGCAUAGAUGCCGUGAUGGUGCUGGGAAAUUCGCAUUUAUUCAUGAAUCGUUCCAACAAACUUGCUGUGAUAGCAAGUCACAUUCAAGAAAGCCGAUUCUUAUAUCCUGGAAAGAAUGGCAGACUUGGAGACUUCUUCGGAGACCCUGGCAACCCUCCUGAAUUUAAUCCCUCUGGGAGUAAAGAUGGAAAAUACGAACUUUUAACCUCAGCAAAUGAAGUUAUUGUUGAAGAGAUUAAAGAUCUAAUGACCAAAAGUGACAUAAAGGGUCAACAUACAGAAACUUUGCUGGCAGGAUCCCUGGCCAAAGCCCUUUGCUACAUUCAUAGAAUGAACAAGGAAGUUAAAGACAAUCAGGAAAUGAAAUCAAGGAUAUUGGUGAUUAAGGCUGCAGAAGACAGUGCGUUGCAGUAUAUGAACUUCAUGAAUGUCAUCUUUGCAGCACAGAAACAGAAUAUUUUGAUUGAUGCCUGUGUUUUAGACUCCGACUCAGGGCUCCUCCAACAGGCUUGUGACAUCACGGGAGGACUGUACCUGAAGGUGCCUCAGAUGCCUUCUCUUCUGCAGUAUUUGCUGUGGGUGUUUCUUCCCGAUCAAGAUCAGAGAUCUCAGUUAAUCCUCCCACCCCCAGUUCAUGUUGACUACAGGGCUGCUUGCUUCUGUCAUCGAAAUCUCAUUGAAAUUGGUUAUGUCUGUUCUGUGUGUUUGUCAAUAUUCUGCAAUUUCAGCCCCAUUUGUACUACGUGCGAGACAGCCUUUAAAAUUUCUCUGCCUCCAGUGCUGAAAGCCAAGAAAAAGAAACUGAAAGUGUCUGCCUGAGGAUAAAAUAUUUUCCCCAUCUUUUAGAGCUGUUAAUAGAAAUUAUAUAGCAGAUUCUUUGUUGGGAAGACUGAAAAAAAUAAAGAUAGGUAUAGGAUAAUUUUUAAUAUGGUGACCUUACAGAAAAUAUUUCCCAAACAUCCUUUUCAUCCUGUGCUUCUGGAGGACUGAUUUGUUUGAGGGAAUCAUUCUAUGCAUUAUAUCCUAAAAUAUUCUAUGACUGGUUUCUGUCCAUGUUUGUGGCUUUCAUUUUUUUAAUGGGAUGACUAUUAGUCAAAGUCAGCUUGUCAUGACUCAUCAUAGGCUUUCUAACCUACUCCCUGAAUCCGGGUCCUCAUUGUGAAAUGCAUGCCAUACGAAAUUUGAACGUAGCUUUGGAAAAAGGGACUAUUUGUGGAGUAAUGGCAUUAAUCAACAUAGAACAUCUUAUUUGAAUCAACAGUUAACUUCAGUAGUCAUGUGAAUAAAAUUCUUAUUGUCUAAAUUGAGACAGCCUCAGAUAUUUGCAGAUAUUUACUUUUUGUCUGAUAUCAGUACAUAUUUGGACAAAGUCAUCUAAAUAAUAGUUUGUCACCAAAUAACUACAAAAUCUCAUUUUAAAUGAGUAAGGAGAACGUGUACAGAAGCAAAUUUUCUUCAAAAUAGUUGUGGGAAGAGCUUAUAUGUGAAAGCUUAUGACUGGUUUUGAGGGAGAACUUACUGGAGAAAAUGGACUCUAUGUUAAGUAUGGUUUUCAGAUAGAAUUCUUUCCUUUUUUAAUGAGGAAAAAAAAUCCACAUUAAUAUUGAAACUGCACCUGUAAUCCCAGCACUUUGGGAGGCUGAGGACAGAGGAUUGCUUGAGCCCAGGAGUUCGAGAGCAGCCUGGGCAGCAAAGUGAGACCCCAUCUCUACUAAAAAUUUAAAUGUAUUUAUUAAAACUGUUCUCUAGAAGCUUUGGACUGAAUCCCAAAAGUGUUUAUAAGUUCAAAAGCAAAAGUAUUUGUAAUUUCAACAACAAAAAAUGUAUUUCUUUAUGUAAUCUUGAAAUUAUUAAAAGUCCUUUUAGCUUCUAGCACAUAUUUGUACAAAGAGUUUAAGGAAUGGUGGCUGGUUUGGUUUGUUUUUUAAAAAUGUUUACUGACGAGGCCGGGCGUGGUGGCUCACCCCUGCAAUCCCAGCACUUUGGGAGGCCGAGGCAGGCAGAUCACAAGGUCAGGAGUUCAAGAUCAGCCUGGCCAGUAUGGUGAAACCCUGUCUCUACUAAAAAUAGAAAAAUUAGCCAUGCGAAGUAGCAGGUGCCUGUAGUUCCAGCUACUCGGGAGGCUGAGGCAAGAGAAUUGCUUGAAUCCAGGAGGCAGAGGUUGCAGUGAGCCAAGAUAGCGCCUCUGUACUCCAGCCUGGGUGACAGAGCGAGACUCUGUAUCAAAAAAAAAAAAGAUCGGGCACGUUGGCUCACGCCUGUAAUCCCAGCACUUUGGGAGGCCAAGGUGGGUGGAUCACGAGGUCAGGAGUGAUCAGGCUGGGUUUCUGUUUUGUUUUGUUUUGUGAGACAGAGUCUCGCUCUGUUGCCCAGGCUGGGGUGCAGUGGUGCAAGCUCGGCUCUCUGCAAGCUCUGUCUCCUGGGUUCACGCCAUUCUCCUGCCUCAGCCUCCCAAGUAGCUGGGAUUACUACUCUACUGAACCCAUGAGGCAGAAAUUUGAGACCAUCCUGCCCAACGUGGUGAAAACAUGGUGAAACCCUGUCUCUACUAAAAAUACAAAAAUUAGCUGGGCGUGGUGGCAGGUGCCUGUAAUCCCAGCUACUCAGGAGACUGAGGCAGGAGAAUUGCUUGAACCCAGGAGGUGGAGGUUGCAGUGAGCCAAGAUCAAGAUUGCGCCAUUGCACUCCAGCCUGGGCGACAAGAACAAAACUCUGUCUCAAAAAAAAAAAAAAAAAAAAAGUCUGUACUGAUAAAACCCAUUGUGUACAAAACUUUGUAUGUAAGGAAGAUUUUAAUUUUCUCUUUAUACAAGCUGAGUCAUAUUUAAAUAAUUUGAUGUUGGCUUAGAUAAUUUCAGAUAGAUUUUAUAUUCUGGAUUUGUGUUUUUGUUAACAAAUAUACAAAGACUUUGGUGAUCACUUUGCAAAUAUUUGUUAAUCCUUGAGUUUGAGAACCUGUCUUUUAAAAAUAAUAUUUUGUAUACUAAUUAAGUGUAAUGGAAAUCACAAUUUUAAGUCUAGGAAAUAAAGUAUUAUAUAUACUUUCAAACAAGCUAGCAAGGCUUUUAUUAUUACUUUUUUAUUUGAAAUAUCUUAUAUAUUUGGUUAGUUCUGUUUAACUUGUUUUUAACUGUUGCCCUUAUGAGUUAUUUUAUAUAAAUUUUUACAAUAAAAUAAUUUGAUUUUCA